CUUCUUCAGAGCACUUCCUACUGAAAGAGGUAUCUCUCUGGAUAGGAAGAAAUAUAGUAGAACCCUUUGAAAAUGGAUAUUUUCACAUAUUUUCGUUCAGAUACAAAAGCUGGCAGUUACUGAAAUAAGGACUUGAAGUUCCUUCCUCUUUUUUUUAUGUCUUAAGAGCAGGAAAUAAAGAGACAGCUGAAGGUGUAGCCUUGACCAACUGAAAGGGAAAUCUUCAUCCUCUGAAAAAACAUAUGUGAUUCUCAAAAAACGCAUCUGGAAAAUUGAUAAAGAAGCGAUUCUGUAGAUUCUCCCAGCGCUGUUGGGCUCUCAAUUCCUUCUGUGAAGGACAACAUAUGGUGAUGGGGAAAUCAGAAGCUUUGAGACCCUCUACACCUGGAUAUGAAUCCCCCUUCUAAUACUUACCAGUCCUUGUAAGAAGAGCUGUCAGUUGUCAGCAAUGGGGAUAAUGCAGUGACCUUAACACCUAUCCGUGGCAUUCUGCAAGGCGCAUUGCACAGAACCCCCUUUCUUUCUUCCAUGAACACGCCUUGCUCUCAGCAGACAGCCAGGUCAGCAUCAGCAGCCAGGUGGUAGCAUCCUGUACUUUCCUGUACUUUCUGGCUCCACCUGGACAAAGUGGUCUGGGCAGACUUUCCUUUUCACCUGCAUGGUUCUACCUGCCUCUUGUCCAAGAUUAAUCUCCCCAUGGUAUCAGGGACCCCACUUCUUCUGGCUUCCUGGGAGAAAGCAGUCCAUGCACCCUCUCCUCACUCUCACUUGUAUUUGUCCUCACUGACCUGCUGACGCAUUCCCCUCGCAGUGGAAUCCUACCCAAGGCCCUCUCAUCUCCAGAAAUGAGCAAACACUUCCUCCUGUCUUCCUGCAUCAUGCAGACUCUAGCAGGCGUGGUUCUUCCCCGCUUCCCACAUUCCCUCUACUCCUCUCUCUCCACCCUGAAGCUCUCCGUUAUCUCACCCCAGCUGCACAUGCUGAGCUUUUGGUGGCCAAACCAAGACUCUUUGGUGGACACUUUUCAGUCCUUCUCAUGCCCAACUCCUCUGCAGCUUCUGAAACUGAUGUCUAGUCUCUCCUCCAAGCUUUCUCUGUCUGGAUUGCCAAGGUGGUCUCUCUGCUCUGCUCCUUGCAUUCCUUUUAGGUUUGUCAUUCUUUAUUUUCCAUUAGCCCUGGCCUACUUUUAAAGGUUGAGGUUCCUCAGGGAAGUUCAUCUGCCCUCCCUUAUGGGGCAACAGAAACAAUCCAGGCUUGUUACAGAUGCCCCAGGCUCCCUCCAGCUGCUGAAACUGAGACCCUGCUCUGAGCCAUAUGCCUCCCCACCCCUCUGCCCUGGGAAUGCUCCAGCUGGAUCCCCAAGAUAUUUCAAAAAUGAAGGGGAUACUCAGGGCAGAGUUCUGAAUCUCAAAACACUCUACUCUGGCAAAGGAAUGAAGUUAUUGGAGUGAUGACAGGAACACGGGAGAACAAUGCUCUGUUUGGGCUGGAUAUUUCUUUGGCUUGUUGCAGGAGAGCGAAUUAAAGGAUUUAAUAUUUCAGGUUGUUCCACAAAAAAACUCCUUUGGACAUAUUCUACAAGGAGUGAAGAGGAAUUUGUCUUAUUUUGUGAUUUACCAGAGCCACAGAAAUCACAUUUCUGCCACAGAAAUCGACUCUCACCAAAACAAGUCCCUGAGCACCUGCCCUUCAUGGGUAGUAACGACCUAUCUGAUGUCCAAUGGUACCAACAACCUUCGAAUGGAGAUCCAUUAGAGGACAUUAGGAAAAGCUAUCCUCACAUCAUUCAGGACAAAUGUACCCUUCACUUUUUGACCCCAGGGGUGAAUAAUUCUGGGUCAUAUAUUUGUAGACCCAAGAUGAUUAAGAGCCCCUAUGAUGUAGCCUGUUGUGUCAAGAUGAUUUUAGAAGUUAAGCCCCAGACAAAUGCAUCCUGUGAGUAUUCCGCAUCACAUAAGCAAGACCUACUUCUUGGGAGCACUGGCUCUAUUUCUUGCCCCAGUCUCAGCUGCCAAAGUGAUGCACAAAGUCCAGCGGUAACCUGGUACAAGAAUGGAAAACUCCUCUCUGUGGAAAGGAGCAACCGAAUCGUAGUGGAUGAAGUUUAUGACUAUCACCAGGGCACAUAUGUAUGUGAUUACACUCAGUCGGAUACUGUGAGUUCGUGGACAGUCAGAGCUGUUGUUCAAGUGAGAACCAUUGUGGGAGACACUAAACUCAAACCAGAUAUUCUGGAUCCUGUCGAGGACACACUGGAAGUAGAACUUGGAAAGCCUUUAACUAUUAGCUGCAAAGCACGAUUUGGCUUUGAAAGGGUCUUUAACCCUGUCAUAAAAUGGUACAUCAAAGAUUCUGACCUAGAGUGGGAAGUCUCAGUACCUGAGGCGAAAAGUAUUAAAUCCACUUUAAAGGAUGAAAUCAUUGAGCGUAAUAUCAUCUUGGAAAAAGUCACUCAGCGUGAUCUUCGCAGGAAGUUUGUUUGCUUUGUCCAGAACUCCAUUGGAAACACAACCCAGUCCGUCCAACUGAAAGAAAAGAGAGGAGUGGUGCUCCUGUACAUCCUGCUUGGCACCAUCGGGACCCUGGUGGCCGUGCUGGCGGCGAGUGCCCUCCUCUACAGGCACUGGAUUGAAAUAGUGCUGCUGUACCGGACCUACCAGAGCAAGGAUCAGACGCUUGGGGAUAAAAAGGAUUUUGAUGCUUUCGUAUCCUAUGCAAAAUGGAGCUCUUUUCCAAGUGAGGCCACUUCAUCUCUGAGUGAAGAACACUUGGCCCUGAGCCUAUUUCCUGAUGUUUUAGAAAACAAAUAUGGAUAUAGCCUGUGUUUGCUUGAAAGAGAUGUGGCUCCAGGAGGAGUGUAUGCAGAAGACAUUGUGAGCAUUAUUAAGAGAAGCAGAAGAGGAAUAUUUAUCUUGAGCCCCAACUAUGUCAAUGGACCCAGUAUCUUUGAACUACAAGCAGCAGUGAAUCUUGCCUUGGAUGAUCAAACACUGAAACUCAUUUUAAUUAAGUUCUGUUACUUCCAAGAGCCAGAGUCUCUACCUCAUCUCGUGAAAAAAGCUCUCAGGGUUUUGCCCACAGUUACUUGGAGAGGCUUAAAAUCAGUUCCUCCCAAUUCUAGGUUCUGGGCCAAAAUGCGCUACCACAUGCCUGUGAAAAACUCUCAGGGAUUCACGUGGAACCAGCUCAGAAUUACCUCUAGGAUUUUUCAGUGGAAAGGACUCAGUAGAACAGAAACCACUGGGAGGAGCUCCCAGCCUAAGGAAUGGUGAAAUGAGCCCUGGAGCCCCCUCCAGUCCAGUCCCUGGGAUAGAGAUGUUGCUGGACAGAACUCACAGCUCUGUGUGUGUGUGUUCAGGCUGAUAGGAAAUUCAAAGAGUCUCCUGCCAGCACCAAGCAAGCUUGAUGGACAAUGGAGUGGGAUUGAGACUGUGGUUUAGAGCCUUUGAUUUCCUGGACUGGACUGACGGCGAGUGAAUUCUCUAGACCUUGGGUACUUUCAGUACACAACACCCCUAAGAUUUCCCAGUGGUCCGAGCAGAAUCAGAAAAUACAGCUACUUCUGCCUUAUGGCUAGGGAACUGUCAUGUCUACCAUGUAUUGUACAUAUGACUUUAUGUAUACUUGCAAUCAAAUAAAUAUUAUUUUAUUAGAAA